AACCGUUCUCGCUAGCGGUGCGCUUCUGGCCUGUUUUGAGUCCGCGCUCAAAGGUCUCUGAGGAUCCCCGGGUGGAAACUCCUCCCGGGAGUAAAACCACACAACCACUGAGAAGACCGCUCCGGCAUCCUAGAGAGUACGCGUGUGAGCCUGGGUGCAAGGCCAAAGUAGUGACGCACUUCCGUUCACGCACCGCUUUCUGUUUUUCCUGAGCCUUUGCCUGCUAAGAGGGAGACCAGGUCAUGGCAGCCAUGCCUCUGAAAGCUCAAUACCAGGAGAUGGUGACCUUCGAGGAUGUGGCUGUGCACUUCACCAAGACAGAAUGGACUGGCCUUUCUCCUGCCCAGAGGGCCCUGUACAGAAGUGUGAUGUUGGAGAAUUUUGGGAACCUGACUGCUUUGGGGUACCCAGUUCCCAAACCUGCACUGAUCUCACUUUUGGAGAGAGGGGACAUGGCUUGGGGCCUGGAAGCACAGGAUGAUCCCCCAGCAGAGAGGACCAAAAACGUCUGUAAAGAUGUUGAGACCAACAUUGACAGUGAGUCCACAUUAAUCCAGGGAAUUUCUGAAGAAAGAGAUGGGAUGAUGUCACAUGGUCAGCUGAAGAGUGUCCCUCAGAGAACUGACUUCCCAGAAACACGUAAUGUGGAAAAGCACCAGGACAUCCCCACAGUGAAAAAUAUCCAAGGAAAGGUUCCAAGAAUCCCCUGUGCAAGGAAACCUUUCAUAUGUGAGGAGUGUGGGAAAUCCUUCAGCUACUUUUCUUACUAUGCUAGACACCAGAGAAUCCACACUGGGGAGAAACCUUUUGAGUGUAGUGAGUGUGGAAAAGCCUUUAAUGGUAAUUCUUCGUUAAUUCGGCACCAGAGGAUUCACACUGGAGAGAGACCCUAUCAGUGUGAGGAGUGUGGGCGAGCCUUUAAUGAUAAUGCAAAUCUGAUCAGGCAUCAGAGAAUCCACAGUGGGGACAGACCCUAUUACUGUACAGAGUGUGGGAAUAGUUUCACGAGUAGUUCCGAGUUUGUUAUACAUCAGAGAAUCCACACUGGGGAGAAACCCUAUGAGUGUAAUGAGUGUGGCAAAGCUUUUGUUGGUAAUUCACCCCUACUUCGGCAUCAGAAAAUCCACACUGGAGAGAAACCCUAUGAGUGUAAUGAGUGUGGCAAAAGCUUUGGAAGGACUUCCCAUCUAAGCCAACAUCAGCGUAUUCACACAGGGGAAAAGCCUUAUUCUUGUAAAGUAUGUGGACAAGCCUUCAAUUUUCAUACAAAACUAACUCGGCACCAGAGAAUUCACAGUGAGGAGAAACCCUUUGACUGUGUAGAUUGUGGAAAAGCCUUCAGUGCUCAGGAACAAUUAAAAAGGCAUCUGAGAAUUCAUACUCAGGAGUCUUCCUAUGUAUGUGAUGAGUGUGGAAAAGCCUUGACUAGCAAAAGAAAUCUUCAUCAGCAUCAAAGAAUCCAUACUGGAGAGAAACCCUAUGAGUGUAGCAAGUAUGAGAAGGCCUUUGGGACUUCUUCCCAGCUAGGUCACCUUGAGCAUGUCUACUCUGGAGAGAAGCCUGUGCUGGACAUUUGUCGUUUUGGCCUCCCAGAAUUUUUUACCCCCUUUUACUGGUAAUAGUACACUCCAGUGAAAUGUACUGAGUGGAUUCCGUCUUCUACUCAGGAAUGGAAUGUGUGACACAGGCCUGACUCAGCCUCUGAUCCAUCCCUCAAGCCACAGUUAAUGAUUCAGAUGUCAGUAGAUGACCAAAGAUGGUUCAAUUAGAGUCCCAGGAUUGCAAGAGCUAAUAGGAACAAAUACUCUCCCCCCGCCCACCCCCAUUGGUUUUAAUGCUGAGAAGAAGAACUAGACUCUUACAGAGGUGAGAAUGAAGUCCACACAGCAAAAAUGCAUCUGAGAAUUGGAGAGCAGUAAAAGACUGAAGAUAAUGUUUGAACAGCCACAUACACCAUGCCUGAAGCUAAAAAUAUAUACGGGUUUUUGAAUUGCAGCAGCCAAUAAAUUCCAUUUUUGUUUGGUUGGUUUUGGCUUUGGCACACCUGAGUUAGGUUUUCUUGCCUUGGAACAGAAUUUUGACUUAAACAGUGUUGUCAUUGUAGCAGUUGUUUGAAGUUUUCAGGGAUAACAUACCUGAUGGAGAAAUGUUUUGUGUGUAUGAUAUAUGGGAAAGUCUUUAGUUAUAGUCAUGGCAGCUCCUCAACCCCAUGAUUGUGAUGAGAUUGGGAAGCCCACUGUAACACUGGAGAGCCCAGGUUAUAUCAGACACCACUAGUAGAUAGAAGUUCUAACAACUUGAGCUCUGUAACAAAAAUCUCAUUGUACUACAAAAUUAUGUCUGCACCAGUGAAUCCAUUCUCAAGAAAAGUCUUAACUAGGAAACUAAAAGCUUUCACUCUUAAAGCUUUCAUUUUCUGUUUAUUCAGUUUUUUAUUUGGAAUGGAUGCUACUCUAGGCCUUAAACUGAGAAAUGCCAGGCUAUUGUAGCUAUUAUAUCUUGGUAUUUGCCAUUUUAAUUCCUAGGACAGCACGCCCGCUUUGCCCUUGACCUGGCUAGGGAGCCAAGGAAAUGCCAUGGUUCUUGGUCAUAAGACACACUGCAGAGAUCUCUCAGUAGGAAAACAGGGCUGGCCCUUUUCUUUGGUGAUGAACACAAACUGCACCCUUUUUUUCUCCCACGUGUCCUUCCGCUGCCAGCCAGUGUUGGAAUCUCCCUACCCAAUUCCAGACUUAAUUGCUUACUGCGUCUAGCACCUGGGUGGCUUCACCACCUCUUCCUUACUUGUCAGCAGAUGAAUGAGCAGUUGUAUCAUGUGCUUGGGUUGACCAAUGAAUGAUAGACUUGGGGAAUUGAGUAAACACCUUUUAAUUGAAGUAUAACACAAACAUAAAAAUGCAUGAGUCAGCCAGGCGCGGUGGCUCACACUUGUAAUCCCAGUACUUUGGGAGGCCGAGGUGGGCGAUUCAUCAGGUCAAGAGAUCGAGACCAUCCUGGCCAACAUGGUGAAACCCCGUCUCUACUAAAAAUACAAGAAUUAGCUGGGCGUGGUGGUGCAUGCCUGUAGUCCCAGCUGCUCAGGAAGCUGGGGCAGGCGAAUUGCUUGAACCCGGGAGGCGGAGGUUGUAGUGAGCCGAGAUUACACCACUGCACUCCAGCCUGGUGACAGAGUGAGAUUCCUCAAUAAAAUAAAAUAAAACCAUGAA